AGCCUAGCACUCUGACCUAGCAGUCAACAUGAAGGCUCUCAUUGUUCUGGGGCUUGUCCUCCUUUCUGUUACGGUCCAGGGCAAGGUCUUUGAAAGGUGUGAGUUGGCCAGAACUCUGAAAAGAUUGGGAAUGGAUGGCUACAGGGGAAUCAGCCUAGCAAACUGGAUGUGUUUGGCCAAAUGGGAGAGUGGUUACAACACACGAGCUACAAACUACAAUGCUGGAGACAGAAGCACUGAUUAUGGGAUAUUUCAGAUCAAUAGCCGCUACUGGUGUAAUGAUGGCAAAACCCCAGGAGCAGUUAAUGCCUGUCAUUUAUCCUGCAGUGCUUUGCUGCAAGAUAACAUCGCUGAUGCUGUAGCUUGUGCAAAGAGGGUUGUCCGUGAUCCACAAGGCAUUAGAGCAUGGGUGGCAUGGAGAAAUCGUUGUCAAAACAGAGAUGUCCGUCAGUAUGUUCAAGGUUGUGGAGUGUAACUCCAGAAUUUUCCUUCUUCAGCUCAUUUUGUCUCUCUCACAUUAAGGGAGUAGGAAUUAAGUGAAAGGUCACACUACCAUUAUUUCCCCUUCAAACAAAUAAUAUUUUUACAGAAGCAGGAGCAAAAUAUGGCCUUUCUUCUAAGAGAUAUAAUGUUCACUAAUGUGGUUAUUUUACAUUAAGCCUACAACAUUUUUCAGUUUGCAAAUAGAACUAAUACUGGUGAAAAUUUACCUAAAACCUUGGUUAUCAAAUACAUCUCCAGUACAUUCCGUUCUUUUUUUUUUUGAGACAGUCUCGCUCUGUCGCCCAGGCUGGAGUGCAGUGGCGCAAUCUCGGCUCACUGCAACCUCCACCUCCCGGGUUCACGCCAUUCUCCUGCCUCAGCCUCCCGAGUAGCUGGGAUUACGGGCGCCCGCCACCACGCCCGGCUAAUUUUUUGUAUUUUUAGUAGAGACAGGGUUUCACCGUGUUAGCCAGGAUGGUCUCGAUCUCCUGACCUUGUGAUCCACCCACCUCGGCCUCCCAAAGUGCUGGGAUUACAGGCGUGAGCCACUGCGCCCGGCCACAUUCAGUUCUUAUCAAAGAAAUAACCCAGACUUAAUCUUGAAUGAUACGAUUAUGCCCAAUAUUAAGUAAAAAAUAUAAGAAAAGGUUAUCUUAAAUAGAUCUUAGGCAAAAUACCAGCUGAUGAAGGCAUCUGAUGCCUUCAUCUGUUCAGUCAUCUCCAAAAACAGUAAAAAUAACCACUUUUUGUUGGGCAAUAUGAAAUUUUUAAAGGAGUAGAAUACCAAAUGAUAGAAACAGACUGCCUGAAUUGAGAAUUUUGAUUUCUUAAAGUGUGUUUCUUUCUAAAUUGCUGUUCCUUAAUUUGAUUAAUUUAAUUCAUGUAUUAUGAUUAAAUCUGAGGCAGAUGAGCUUACAAGUAUUGAAAUAAUUACUAAUUAAUCACAAAUGUGAAGUUAUGCAUGAUGUAAAAAAUACAAACAUUCUAAUUAAAGGCUUUGCAACACA